AUACGUAGCGGCCGCCAUUGUUCCGCGCCGAUGGCGAGAUCCUUGUUCCUCAGAUAGCGUUCAUCGCCCGUCGUGGUCAACGGGCCAGCCGAGUCUGGAGUGGUUGCGAACCCUUCUGGCUGCAGAUCUGGAGGUGGAGGCAGUACCCUGGACUCUAUUCUGCUGCCCCUUCAGGGUUUGGAGGAGCCGGAGCAUCCCUCGCGUCCUGUCACUUCCAGCGAGGCACACAAAACUGACCGUAGGGAUGGCCACCAGGGUCCGGACAGCUUCUAUUUGGGUCCCACCUCUCCAAGAACGAAACAGUUCAUGGGAUAGGAUCAGAAAGCUCCAAGGUCAGGAAUCCAUCUUGGGCCAAGGGACUCCUGGUCUGCAACCUCUCCCUGGAACACCCAGGCAGAAGCAGAAGAGUCGCAGAAUAGAGAAAGUCCUAGAGUGGCUGUUUAUUUCCCAAGAGCAGCCAAAAAUCACCAAGUCCUGGGGACCUUUGUCAUUCAUGGAUGUGUUUGUGGAUUUUACCUGGGAGGAGUGGCAGCUGCUAGACCCAGCACAGAAGUGCCUGUACAGGAGUGUGAUGUUGGAGAACUAUAGCAACCUGGUGUCCCUAGGGUACCAACACACCAAACCUGAUAUCAUCUUCAAGUUGGAACAAGGAGAAGAGCUGUGUAUGGUGCAGGCCCAAGUUCCAAAUCAGACCUGUCCAAUUUUGAAGGCUGGAAAGUCCAAAGCCAAGGUGCUGGCAGGUUUGGUGUCUGGUGAGGGCCUGCUCUGUGCUUCCAAGAUGACGCCUUGUUGCUGCAUCCUCUGGAGACACAGUCUGGAAAAUUGAUGAUCUUAUGGAUUGGCAUCAGGAAAAUAAAGACAAGCUGGGAAGUACGGCAAAAAGCUUUGAAUGCACUACAUUUGGAAAACUAUGUCUUCUUAGUACAAAGUAUCUUUCAAGACAAAAACCUCAUAAAUGUGGCACGCAUGGAAAGAGUUUGAAAUAUAUAGAUUUCACUAGUGAUUAUGCUAGAAAUAAUCCUAAUGGGUUUCAGGUACAUGGAAAAUCAUUCUUCCAUUCUAAACAUGAGCAAACUGUUAUUGGAAUAAAAUACUGUGAAAGUAUUGAAUCUGGAAAAACCGUCAAUAAGAAAUCGCAACUUAUGUGCCAACAAAUGUAUAUGGGCGAAAAACCCUUUGGAUGCAGCUGUUGUGAGAAAGCCUUCAGCAGCAAGUCAUACCUUCUAGUGCAUCAGCAAACUCAUGCCGAAGAGAAACCCUAUGGUUGUAAUGAAUGUGGGAAAGACUUCAGUAGUAAAUCAUACCUCAUUGUACAUCAGAGAAUUCAUACAGGAGAGAAACUACAUGAAUGCAGUGAAUGCAGGAAAACAUUCAGUUUCCAUUCACAGCUUGUUAUACAUCAGAGAAUUCACACAGGUGAGAAUCCCUAUGAGUGCUGUGAAUGUGGGAAAGUCUUCAGUAGGAAAGACCAGCUUGUUUCACACCAGAAAACUCAUUCAGGACAGAAACCAUAUGUGUGUAAUGAAUGUGGGAAAGCUUUUGGUUUAAAAUCACAGCUCAUUAUACAUGAAAGAAUUCAUACAGGAGAGAAACCAUAUGAAUGCAAUGAAUGUCAGAAAGCCUUUAAUACAAAGUCAAACCUUAUGGUACAUCAGAGAACCCAUACAGGGGAGAAACCUUAUGUUUGUAGUGAUUGUGGAAAAGCCUUUACAUUCAAGUCACAGCUCAUUGUACAUCAGGGGAUUCACACAGGAGUAAAGCCCUAUGGGUGUAUUCAGUGUGGUAAAGGAUUCAGUUUGAAAUCACAGCUCAUUGUACAUCAGAGAAGUCACACAGGAAUGAAACCUUAUGUAUGCAAUGAAUGUGGCAAAGCCUUCAGGAGCAAGUCAUACCUUAUUAUACAUACAAGGACUCAUACAGGAGAAAAACUCCAUGAAUGCAACAAUUGUGGGAAAGCCUUCAGUUUUAAAUCACAGCUCAUUAUACAUCAGAGGAUUCAUACAGGAGAGAACCCCUAUGAAUGCCAUGAAUGUGGGAAAGCCUUCAGUCGGAAAUACCAGCUUAUUUCACACCAGAGAACUCAUGCAGGAGAGAAGCCUUAUGAAUGCACCGACUGUGGAAAGGCUUUUGGUUUAAAGUCACAGCUUAUUAUACACCAGAGAACUCAUACAGGGGAGAAACCAUUUGAAUGUAGUGAGUGUCAGAAAGCCUUUAAUACAAAGUCAAACCUGAUUGUACAUCAGAGAACUCAUACAGGAGAGAAACCCUAUAGUUGUAAUGAAUGUGGAAAAGCCUUUACGUUCAAAUCACAGCUCAUUGUACAUAAAGGAGUGCACACUGGAGUAAAACCCUAUGGAUGCAGUCAAUGUGCAAAAACCUUUAGUUUGAAGUCCCAGCUCAUUGUACAUCAGAGAAGUCACACAGGAGUAAAACCAUAUGGAUGCAGUGAGUGUGGGAAAGCCUUCAGGAGCAAGUCAUACCUUAUUAUACAUAUGAGAACUCAUACAGGAGAGAAACCACAUGAGUGCAGGGAAUGCGGGAAAUCCUUUAGUUUCAAUUCACAACUCAUUGUGCAUCAGAGAAUUCACACAGGAGAAAAUCCCUAUGAAUGCAGUGAAUGUGGGAAAGCCUUUAAUAGGAAAGACCAGCUCAUUUCACAUCAGCGAACUCAUGCAGGGGAAAAGCCUUAUGGGUGCAGUGAAUGUGGGAAAGCUUUUAGCAGCAAGUCAUACCUAAUUAUACACAUGAGAACUCAUUCAGGUGAAAAACCAUAUGAAUGUAAUGAAUGUGGGAAAGCCUUCAUUUGGAAAUCACUACUCAUUGUACAUGAGCGAACUCAUGCAGGGGUCAACCCUUAUAAAUGCAGUCAAUGUGAGAAAUCCUUCAGUGGGAAAUUACGCCUUCUUGUACACCAGAGAAUGCACACAAGAGAGAAACCAUAUGAAUGCAGUGAGUGUGGAAAAGCCUUCAUUAGGAAUUCUCAACUCAUUGUACAUCAAAGAACUCAUUCAGGAGAGAAACCCUAUGGGUGCAAUGAAUGUGGGAAAACCUUCUCUCAAAAAUCAAUUCUCAGUGCACAUCAGAGAACACAUACAGGAGAGAAGCCUUGUAAGUGCACUGAAUGUGGGAAAGCCUUUUGUUGGAAGUCACAGCUCAUUAUGCAUCAGAGAACUCAUGUAGAUGACAAACAUUGAUAAUUUUACGAAACUCUGAAAAGUGGAUUCACAAGAGAUAGAAACAAUCAUAUAUAAAGAGAAACUCUGUAAGUGGAAUCAUCUUGUCAUCUUCCAGAAAACUCAUACUGAAUAGAAACUUUAUGAAUGCACAGCAUAUGGAAAGGCAUCCACAGAAAGCUGUUCUUUACAUGCAAAAAGAUAGUAGACAAUACACAGGAAAACUGAAUUUAGUAACCACUCUGAAAAUUUUUAGCAGCAAGUCAUACCUUUUUUUAAAAAGUUCAUACAGGUGAGGAACCAUGUUAAACGUUGUAAAGUCAUUUUACUAAAAUAAGAUUCACAAAGAGGAAACUUCAUGAACCAGAUGAAUAUAGAAUAGACUUCUUUGAAAUUCAUAGUUUACAGAAUUUUAAUGAGAGAAAUUAUUGAGCUAAUGAAUGGCAGAAUUAACAAAAUUACAAACAUUUUAUGUAUCGGAAGCAUAUACCUUGGAGGGACCAUGCUAUAAGGGAAAGUGUAAAUCUAGAAAUGAGAAACCCCUAGGGAAAAAAUAUAUAUAGGAGUGAACAUCUUAUGAAUGUACCAAAUAAACCACAGCUGGACUGUUAACCUCACCUUAGAAGCUUCAUUCUAAAAAAAAAAAAAAAAAAAAAAAAAAAAACCAACCUGUUAUUAUAUCUUAAUAUUAAUUUUGAAGAAUUAUUUCUUUUAGGAAUCAUUUUAAGAAAUUUUAUUCCAGGUGUUCCAAAAUUUCAGGAAAAGGUUUGAGAAAAUUCUCAAUUAUAAAUAAUAAGAUACAGAUUAUUUCAUUGUACAAGUGAAUCUAGUAAGGAGGUUAAGAAUAAGAAAUAACAUCCCAGAGCCUACAGGGAUAUUUAGAUAUCUUCCUAUGUGUACUACAUAAUAUGAAUUUUGCAGUUUGGCAUUUUACUUGCGAAUGCCAUAUGUGAGACAAAAAUCAUCUUCCAGAGAUUUCAGUAUCUCUGAUACUGACAAUAUCUCUGAUAUGACAAUAUCAUCUUCCAGAGAUUUCUACUCUGCAUACCAACAUUGUUUCUUUGUGUCUUACCAAAUGCAACUUGUUACUAGAAUAUGACUUACUAAAAAUGCAUUUCCACACUGCAAACAUUUUUUAGGGCUAUCUUCUGCCCUUUGGAAGCAGUCUUGGCAGCAACCUCUUUAGUAAUCAAUAUAAGGCACACUUCAUGUGUUUGUGUAGCCUGGAAUCUAUUCUACCUUCACAGGUUAGAACAUCUUGAUUUCCUCUUAACGAAACAUUCCCUAACGGUGUAUGUAGUCAUGAGGGAACCACCAUUCAAGAUGCCCUGCUCAGGACUUGGCAUGAGCACUAUGGUCAGCUGAGGCUCAGAACUGUACAUUGUUAAUGGGUUUUUCAAGUUCAGAAAAGCAACAUGAGCUUUUGUUCUGUGGUAGCAUGUUGAUGUAAUAAGUAGCUAUUUCAAUAGAGGUUCCCAGAACAGCUUUUGUUACUGUCAUUUUCUUAACUUUGUUCACUUGUCUUUUAUUUUGAGCUAUUGGGUGUGCUUUUAAUACAUUCCUUGUUUGAUUGCAUUAGCCAUUGUGUAUCUUUUGCAUACAGCUUACUAAAUCAGAUGGCUUCAGAAAUGGGUGGUAGAGGAGUAGGCAGAAACUUGCAAGGAUAUGUGGAUAUUUGGAAAUGGUUGUUUCCCAAGACAGGAUGGAAGUCUUUUAAGCAAGAAACUUGGCCCAUGCUAUGAAGUCAUGAAAUGAAUUGUUGGCAUCAUGUGCUCACUGAGGCUUUGGGGAAAUGGAUAAGUUGUCAUUGAAAAAUUUUAAACAGAAUUCUGGAGUGGUCAAGAGGGGAAUGCUUUUGAUACCCAUGUAUAACAUGGAGAAUAAUGAUCUUAAAACUUCAAUUUAAGAUUAUGUGUCAGUGAUACUACUUAGUUACAUGUAGCUAUAGAGUCACAGUGGUGAAAAACUCUGCCAGUUGCUUACUCACAAAGUUAGUUUUCUUCACUACCUCAUCAGGUUUGUUAUGUGAGUGGGCAUUAAUCUGGGAAGAGUGGGACCCUGCCAGUUAGAUUAGGGCUAUCUUGGAGGAAUAUGCGGAUUCAAUACUGCAAAUAUUUCUGAAACACCUUCUGCUUUGUACUCUAUUAGAUACCCAAAGAAAUUUUCAUCCUUGAAGCGGAGGAAUUUAAUGAUACCUGAAUGCCUAACUGUUGUAUUCUGCUUAUACAGAAUCCAAUCUCAAGAUACUUGGGGUGAAGAAUGAUGAUUCACAGAAGGGAAGGGACAUCUUACAUAAACAAAUAAUCGCAGAUACUUGCUAAAGUGUAUCCCCCAAUCUGGGAAAUACUGUAAAGGUGUAUAUUAUUAUUGAUGUACCAAAGAAGACAGAAUAAAUUCAUAAGAGAAAGUUUAUAUUCAGUUUACUACUACCUAGGGUUAGAUUUUAGUUUGUUGUUUUUUCAGAUGCAAAUCUACAUGCAGCCUUGCCUGGUAGAAGCCAGAAGUGUUGACAGUAUUGAGGACAGCACUCACAUACUGUGGGAAAGAAUAAUACUUGAUUAGGACUUAUUAUUUAAUGAAAUGAAAAUUUUACAAAACAGAAAUUGAGUUACUGGUUUGUAAAUCUAUCUAGUCCUUCUACCCCAGCCCCAGAAAAGAAAGACAUUCCAGAGACUUUUCAGGAAUAGUUAUUAUAAGGAAAAUCCAAGGAAAAAUAACCCCAAUAUUUUACAACUUCCCCAUCAAAUAGAAAUUUAGGAGAAAAAAUGACUUGCAAACCAUAUUUGUGAACAUAGGUUUAAAAAUCCAUAUUUGUGAACAUAGGUUUAAAAAUCCAUAUUUGUGAACAUAGGUUUAAAAAUUCUAAAUGGAAUUAUAGCAAACCAAUGUAUAGCUAACAAGAAAGUCAUGAUAUUAGGUUUAACAGACUAUUAGUGGAUCCAGCAUCCUUUGUUCAUUACCAGCAGAAUCACUAUUAUUUAUAAUGGCAGUAUGCCCACUUAAAAAGAGAUAUAUGGGGCCAGGCACGGUGGCUCACACCUAUAAUCCCAGCACUUCAGGAGGCUGAGAUGGUGGAUCACCUGAGGUCAGGAGUUUGAGACCAGCCUGGCCAACAUGGUGAAACCCCUCUCUACUAAAAAUACAAAAAAAUAGCAGGGCAUGGUAACUGACACCUAUAAUCCCAGCUACUUGGGAGGCUGGGACGGGAGAAUCACUUGAAUCUAGGAGGCGGAAGUUGCAGUGAGCUGAGAUCGUACCACUGUACUCCACCCUGGGUGACAGAACUAGACCCUGUCUCAAAAAACAGAAGAGUAUGUUUGGAAGAUUUAAUAUUAGAAAAUAUUUUAAUUAACUACCAGAUAAAACUCAUAAGGAUUAUCUCAGUAUAUGCUGAUAAAUCACUUGAUGGAAUUUAACACCCAUAGAUGACACUAAAAUACUAUUAAGUUGGGAAUUAAAAUUAACUCCUGUAACUUGGUAGGGAAUAUAUGUUCUGAAAACACAAAUGUCAUACUUAAUGAUAAAAUAGUAGAAAGAUUCCUUUAAAGUAAAAUUAGCCAGGUGCAGUGGCUCAUCCAUGUAAUACCAGCACUUGGGAAGGCUGAGGCUGGAGGAUUGCUGGAACCCAGGAGUUCGAGACAAGCCUGACCAAUAUAGGGAGACCCUGUCUGUACAAAAACUUUUUAAAAAGAUUAGCCAGGUGUGGUCAGGCGCCGUGGCUCAUGCCUGUAAUCCCAGCACUUUGGGAGGCCGAGGUGGGCAGAUCACUUGAGGUCAGGAUUUCAAGACCAGUGUGGCUAACAUGGUGAAACCCCGUCUCUACUAAAAAUACAAAAGUCAGCCAGGUGUGGUGGCACGUGCCUGUAAUCCCAUCUACUCGGGAGGCUGAGGCAGAAGAAUUGCUUGAACCUAGGAGGUGGCAGUUGCAGUGAGCCAAGAUUGCACCACUGCACUCCAGGCUGGGCGACAGAACAAGCCUCCAUCUCAAAAAAAAGAUCAGCCAGGUGUAGUGGCAAGUGCCGGUAGUCCCACCUACUGAGGAGGCUGAGGCAGGAGGUUAGCUUGAGUCCAGUAGUUCAAGGCUACAGUGAGCUAUGAUCAUGCCCCUGCACUCCAUCCUGGGCAACAAAGUGAGACCCUGUCUGUAAAAAACAAAGCAAAAUUACAAGAAUGCGCAUCACUUUUAUGAAAUGAGUAACAUCUAGCCAAGGUGUGAAAACAAGGAAUGUGAGGAAUUAGGGAUGGGUGCAGAAACAACUGCCAUGAAUUGGAGAUGUGAUCGUGUAAUUAGGAAACCCAAAAUAAACCACAAACAAAUGUUUGGAACUGCCAGUAGAGUAGCAAGUAUGCAGUUGUCAGUAUUCAUGGAGGACCCCCCCGCAACCACAGAUACUCCCUGUGGAUGCUCAAGCUCCUUAUAUGGCAUAGUAUUUGCAUUUUUUUUUUUUUUUUUGAGAUGGAGUCUCGCUGUAUUGCCAGGCUGGAGUGCAGUGGUGUGUUCUUGGCUCACUGCAACCUCUGCCUCCUGGGUUCAAGCAAUUCUCCUGCCUCAGCCUCCCUAGUAGCUGGAAUUACAGGCACACGCCACCACGCCCAGCUAAUUUUUGUGUUUUUAGUAGAGAUGGGGUUUCACCAUGUUGGCCAGGCUGGUCUUGAACUCCUGACCUCGUGAUCCACCCUCAGCCUCCCAAAGUGCUGGGAUUACAGGUGUGAGCCACUGGUCUGUAUUGAUUUUUCUUAAUUCUUUGCUAAAGGGCCAGGUAGAGUUAUUUAUUUCUUGUAGAGAUGGGGUUUUACCAUGUUUUCCAGUCUGGUUUCAAACUCCUGGGCUCAAGCAGUCCACCUGCCUUGGCCUCCCAAAGUGCUAGGAUUACAGGUGUGAGCCAAGCACCCAGCCAUAAAUCUUAAAUAAAUUCUGAUUUUGGUAUAAAUGAUAUAUUUAAAUUUAAAUGAAGUUGCAAGUUUUAACAUGUCUACUCUUUAAUUUUCAACAUUGUUUCAACUACUUGUUAGAAACACAGGCCAUUAAAACAUUAAUAAAAAGGCUGGGCAUGGUGGCUCAUGCCUGUAAUCUCAGCAUUUUGUGAGGCUGAGGCAGGUGGAUGACUUGAGGUCAGGAGUUCGAGACCAGCCUGGUGAAACCCCGUCUCUACUAAAAAUACAAAAAUUGGCCAGCUGUGGUGGCAUGCAUCUAUAAUCCAAGCUACUCAGGAGAAUUGCUUGAACUGGAGAGGCGGAGGUUGCAGUGAGCUGAGAUUGUGCCAUUGCACUCCAGCCCGGGCAGCAGAGUGAGACUCCUUCAAAAAAAAUUAAUAAAAGCAAGCACAUAGGGUGCACAUUUGCCCUUCCCUCUUGGGAUCCAGGGUGAUCCCACAGGUGCUGUUCAUCCCCAACUUUGACCUGGACUGUUGCAGUGUUUUGUCGCAGUGUUUCUCCCUUUUUUUGUACUGGGAUUUCUCCCCAGAAACAAACCCAUAUGUAUAAAAAGUAGUUGGGCUUGCUAUAAAGAUGACUAGUGGAAACCUCAAUAGAGGUACGAUUUCCUAAAAUAAAUCUUGUUCAGAUAUUACAGGGCAAAGUGAAACAGCAAAGCUCCCUCCUCAGCACUCAGGGUGCAGGCCUCACUUUUCCUCAUCUUUUCCUCCUGUGGCCUCCAUGUAUCCCAAAGGUGAGAUGACAUCGCCCCAGAUUGGUCCGGAAAGUGCACUGGUCGUCACUGUGGGUGUACCCUACAGGAGUCUUCAGAUAUGGAAGCUCUGGAUCUCACUGUGAUGUAUCCCCCUAGGGGGUCCCCAGGUUGUGAGGAAAAGGAAGCUUUAGUCCUCACUGUGGUUGCAUCCCCCACCACGGGUCAGUCCUGAGGAGGAUACUCUGGUCAUCACUGUGAUCUACCUCCCAGGGGUCCCCAGGUUGGUCCUGAGGAGAAGGAAGCUCAGAACCUCACUGUGGAUUUGCCCCACUAGGGUCCCUAGGUCAGUCCUGAAGAGAAACAAGCUCCAGUCUUCACUGUGGUUGUGCCCCACAGUGGUCCUCAGGUUGGCCAGUGGAGAAGGAAGCUCUGGUUCUCAGUGUGAUGCAUCCCCCAGGUUGGUCCUGAGAUGAGGUAAAUUCUGGUCAUCACUGUGAAGUGCCCUCGGGGGUCUCCGGGUCCUGAGUAGAAGCAAGGUCUGUUUGUCACUGUGGAUUCCCCCCUGCCAAGGGUCCCCAGGUCAGUCCUGAGGAGAAGGCAGCUCAGUCUUUACUGUGAUGCAGCCUCUAGUGAUCCCCAGGUCCUGAGUAGAAGGAAGGCCUGGUCCUCUGUGGAUUCAACCCAGAGGUCUGUGAGCAGAAUGCAGGUACUGCAAGCAGGCUAGACAAGGUGUGUGCUUGCACCCCUUCCUUACUACCUAGGCACAGUGUUGGAUGGUCAGUGCUUCCUGUUUUGUGAUGGCCAUGUGCCCCCUCUUGCAGUCCCAGUGAACCCCUGAAAUUCAAUCUUACGAUUUUCCAUGCCAUAAUUUUGGAAAACGAAACUGAAAUAGAGUCCAUCAUUCCAUGCCUUAAUUGGAAUGGAUAGAGAUAAUAAAAGGCAAAGUAGAUGGCCAUAGACAAAAGUCAAGUGAUUUCCUAUAUAUUUGAAAUAAUGUAUAGCAAUAAUUGGAAUUUGUAAUGAAUAAAAUCAUUCAAAAAAAUCUGAAAAAGUGUUUGUAUGCAAAAUAUAAAAAAAAAACCCUAAAAUUGAACAAGAAGACAACCCAAUUAAAAAUGGGGACAGAUCCAAAUACAUACUUUCCAAAGAUAUACAGAUGGUGGCCAGGCACGGUGGCUCACGCCUGUAAUCCCAGCACUUUGGGAGGCCGAGGCGGGCAGAUCACCUGAGGUCCGGAGUUCGAGACCAGCCUGACCAACAUGGAGAAACCCUGUCUCUACUAAAAAUACAAAAUUAGCCAGGCGUGGUGGCGCUACUCUGCCACCAAGUGGUAGCUACUCCGGAGGCGGAGGCAGGAGAAUGGCUUGAACCCGGGAGGCGGAGGUUGCUGUGAGCCGAGAUCGCGCCAUUGCACUCCAGCCUGGGCAACAAGAGUGAAACUCCGUCUCAAAAAAAAAAAAAAGAAGAUAUACAGAUGGCAAAUAAGCAUACCAAAUAAUGCUCAGUGACACUUGUCAUGAGGGAAAAGCAAAUUAAAACAACGAGAUAGCACCGCACAUCUAUUAAAGUGACUAUAAUCUAAAAAUAAGUAAAUUUGCAAUUGCAACAGGAACUCUCAUUCAUUGCUGGUGCAAUGCAUAAUAGUAUAGCCACUUUGGAAGAUAGUUUGACUUUUCCCCAAAGCUAAACAAAGCUUCACAAUAUGAGCCAACAAUCACACUCCUAGGUAUUUAGAUAACUGCUUUGAAAACAUAGGAGUUUGAUCUAAACAAAACCCAGCAUGUACUCACGUACAGCAGCUCUUUUCAUAACAGACAAAUACUUUAAGGAAUCAGGAUAACCUUCAAUAGGUGAAUGACUAACUAGGCUGGGGUACAUCCAUGCAAUGGAGUCCUGUUCAGCAAGAGCAAGCUCUGAGGCCAUGCAGGACAUGGAUGAAUCUGAUAGGCAUAUUGCUAAGUGAAAGAGACCAGUGUGAAAAGGCUGUAUGAUCCUAUUUCUAUGAUGUUAUGGAAAAGCAGAAACUACAGGGGUAGCAAACAUAUCUGUGAUUGAUGACGGUUUGUAGAGGGCAGGGAGUGAGUUAAAUAGGAGGAUAUAAUGAUAGAAACAGGCACAAAUGGGCCUUUGGAGAGUGUACUCCCUCUGCUUGGUGAAAUUAUGCUGGGUGUGUGUGGAAGAGCCUGGGAUGUAUAAUGCCAGCAUGAACAAAAAGGCCACUUAUCACUCCAGGAGAGCAGGGUGUUCUUUCAUCACACAUGAAAUUAUUUCAGGAUCAGUUCCAAGGGAGACUUUCAUGUGUGAUUUUAUAUAUAUAUAUAUAUAUAUAUAUAUAUAUAUAUAUAUAUAUAUAUAUAUAUGUAUAUAUACACACACACAUACACACAUAUAUACACAUAUAUAUACACAUAUACACAUAUAUAUACACAUAUAUAUAAUAAGAACAUUUACCAUUUUAACUAUUUUUAAGUGUACACUUCAGUGGCAUGAAGUACAUUAUUUCCAUUAUUGUGCAACUAUCAUUUUACAUUCCACCAGCAGUGCACAAGGCUUCCAAUUUCUCCACAUACUUGCCAAUAUUAAUUAGUUUGUUUCUCUCUCAUUUCAUAGGCAUGAUCAUAACUCACUGCAGCCCCAACCUCCUGGGCUCAAGGGAUCCUUCCACCUCAGCCUCCUGGGUAGCUGGAACUACAGGUGCCACUACACCCAAAUAGUUUUUUGGUUUUUUUGAAAUGGAGUUUCACUCUGUCACCCAGGCUGGAGUGCAGUGGCACCAUUUCAGCUCACUGCAACCUCCGCCUCCUAGGUUUAAGUGAUUCUCCUUCCUCGGCCUCCUGAGUAGCUGGGAUUACAGGCAUGUGCCACCAUGUAUGGCUAUUUUUUGUAUUUUUAGUAGAGACAGGGUUUCACCAUGUUGGCCAGGCCAGGCUAGUCUCAAACUCCUGUCCUCAAGUGAUCCACUUACCUUGGCCUCCCAAAGUGCUGGGAUUACAGGCUUGAACCACUGCACUUGGCCUCCAUAUUUUUUAUAAUAGCCACUCUAACAUGUAUGAAAUGGUAUCUCAUUGUGGUUUUGAUUUUCCUUUACCUAAUGGCUAGUGAUGUUGAAAAUCUUUUCAUGUACUUCUUGGCACUGGAUUUGGCAAUGAUUUAUUGGAUAUGACACCAGAAGCAUGGGAAACAAAAGAAAAAAUAGGUAAAUUGGACUUCACCAAAAUUGAAAACUUUCGGCAUCAGUGGACACUAUCAAGAAAGUGAAAAGGAGCUGGGUGUGGUGGCUCACGCCUGUAAUUCCAGCACUUUGGGAGGCCAAGGUGGGAGGAUCACUUGAGGUCAGGAGUGCGAGACCAGCCUGGUUAACUUGGUGAAACCACGUCUCUACUAAAAAUAAAAAAAAAGAGAAAAAAAAAAGCCGGGUGUGGUGGCAUGUGCCUGUAAUCCCAGCAACUCAGGAAGCUGAGGCAGGAGGAUCGCUUGAAGCUGUGAGGUGGAGGUUGCAGUGAGCCGAGAUCAUGCUACUGCACUCCAGCCCAGGUGACAGAGCAAGAAAGCAAAAUUCCAUCUCAAAAAAAAAAAAAAGGCCGGGUGUGGUGGCUCACGCCUGUAAUCCUAGCACUUUGGGAGGCUGAGGCAGGUGGAUCACGAGGUCAGGAGAUCGAAACCAUCCUGGCUAAUGUGGUGAAACCCUGUCUCUACAAAAAAAUACAAAAAAUUAGCCAGGCUGGUAGUGGAAGCCUGUAGUCCCAGCUACUUGGGAGGCUGAGGAAGGAGAAUGGCGUGAACCUGGAACCAGUGAGCCCAGAUCUCACCACUGCACUCCAGCCUGGGCGACAGAGCGAGACUCCGUCUCAAAAAAAAAAAAGGUGAAUAUAGGAGAAAAGACACUGUAAAAUAAUAUACCUGAUAAGGGUCUAGUAUCCAGAACAUAUAAAGAACUCUUACAACCCAACAACAAAAAGACAACCCAAUAUCAAAAUGGGCAGAGGACUUGAAGAGACUUUUCUGUAAAGAAGAUAUGCAAAUAGCAUAUGAAACGAUACUCAACAUCACUAGCCAUCAUGGAAAUAUAAAUCAAAAAUACAAUGAGAUAACACUCCAUACCCAUCAGAAUGUCUUAUUAUUUUAAAAACAAACCAGAAACAAGUAUUGACAAAGAAGUGGAGAAAUGUGAACACCGCUGUAAAAUGGUAAAGCUGCUAUGACUGACCCUUGCUACAACGUGGAGGAACCUCAGAAACAUUGUGCUGAGAACCCAGCACAAGGCCACACACCUGUAAUCCCAGCUACUCGGGAGGCUGAGGUGGGAGGGUCGCUUGAGCCUGGGAGUUCAAGUCCAGUCUGGGCAGCAUAGCAAGACUCCAUGUCUACAAAGAUAAAAAUAAAAGCAAUGUGCAGAAAGAGGCUGGCCACAAAAAGGUCACAUACUGUAUGAUACCACUUAUAUGAAAUACCCAGAAUGGGUAAAUCCAAAGAGAGCAUAUUGGUGGUUGUCAAGGGUCGGAGGGAGGAUGAAAUGUGUGACAGCUGCUUAAUGGAUGGAGGAUUUCCUUUGGGGUGAUGAAACUAUUUUGGAACUAAGAGGUGGUGGCUGCACAAUGUUGUGCAUGGACUAAAUGUCACAGAAAUGUACAUUUUUAAAAGUUAAUUUUAUAUUGUGUAAAUUUUACCUCAAUAAAAAAAUCUAGUCCACAGCA